GGCCGGGCGGGCAUGGGCCUUCCCGGCCCGGAGCUGGGAGUCGAAGGGGCGGGAGGCGUGAUGGUGAACUCGCAAGAAGUUUGAGGGACGCGCGGGCCCCGCGCCCACUCCCCCUCCACCGGACACGGCUGGGGCCGGCGAUGCCUGAGAGGGGGUCGGAGGACGCAGUGAACAUAUAUGCAUGUACAGUGUGGAUCCUCAUCUGAGAGGAGGGAGAUGAAAACACACCCACCUCACAGGCUGUUGUGAGGACUAAGGGUGCGGCAGUGCCUGGUACAUGGGAGCCAGCGCCGGCAGCCACCAUGGCGUCACGCAUAGGGUUGCGCAUGCAGCUCAUGCGGGAGCAGGCGCAGCAGGAGGAGCAGCGGGAGCGCAUGCAGCAACAGGCUGUCAUGCAUUACAUGCAGCAGCAGCAGCAGCAGCAACAGCAGCAGCUCGGAGGGCCGCCCACCCCGGCCAUCAAUACCCCCGUCCACUUCCAGUCGCCACCACCUGUGCCUGGGGAGGUGUUGAAGGUGCAGUCCUACCUGGAGAAUCCCACAUCCUACCAUCUGCAGCAGUCGCAGCAUCAGAAGGUGCGGGAGUACCUGUCCGAGACCUAUGGGAACAAGUUUGCUGCCCACAUCAGCCCAGCCCAGGGCUCUCCGAAACCCCCACCAGCCGCCUCCCCAGGGGUGCGAGCUGGACACGUGCUGUCCUCCUCCGCUGGCAACAGUGCUCCCAAUAGCCCCAUGGCCAUGCUGCACAUUGGCUCCAACCCUGAGAGGGAGUUGGAUGAUGUCAUUGACAACAUUAUGCGUCUGGACGAUGUCCUUGGCUACAUCAAUCCUGAAAUGCAGAUGCCCAACACGCUACCCCUGUCCAGCAGCCACCUGAAUGUGUACAGCAGCGACCCCCAGGUCACAGCCUCCCUGGUGGGCGUCACCAGCAGCUCCUGCCCUGCGGACCUGACCCAGAAGCGAGAGCUCACAGAUGCUGAGAGCAGGGCCCUGGCCAAGGAGCGGCAGAAGAAAGACAAUCACAACUUAAUUGAAAGGAGACGAAGGUUCAACAUCAAUGACCGCAUCAAGGAGUUGGGAAUGCUGAUCCCCAAGGCCAAUGACCUGGACGUGCGCUGGAACAAGGGCACCAUCCUCAAGGCCUCUGUGGAUUACAUCCGGAGGAUGCAGAAGGACCUGCAAAAGUCCAGGGAGCUGGAGAACCACUCUCGCCGCCUGGAGAUGACCAACAAGCAGCUCUGGCUCCGUAUCCAGGAGCUGGAGAUGCAGGCUCGAGUGCACGGCCUCCCUACCACCUCCCCGUCCGGCAUGAACAUGGCUGAGCUGGCCCAGCAGGUGGUGAAGCAGGAGCUGCCUAGCGAAGAGGGCCCAGGGGAGGCCCUGAUGCUGGGGGCUGAGGUCCCUGACCCUGAGCCACUGCCAGCUCUGCCCCCGCAAGCCCCGCUGCCCCUGCCCACCCAGCCACCAUCCCCAUUCCAUCACCUGGACUUCAGCCACAGCCUGAGCUUUGGGGGCAGGGAGGACGAGGGUCCCCCGGGCUACCCCGAACCCCUGGCGCCGGGGCAUGGCUCCCCAUUCCCCAGCCUGUCCAAGAAGGAUCUGGACCUCAUGCUCCUGGACGACUCACUGCUACCGCUGGCCUCUGAUCCACUUCUGUCCACCAUGUCCCCCGAGGCCUCCAAGGCCAGCAGCCGCCGGAGCAGCUUCAGCAUGGAGGAGGGCGAUGUGCUGUGACCCUGGCUGCCCCUGUGCCAGGGAACAGGGGCCGGCCUGGGGGCUGGGAGGGCCAGGGGCACCUCCCUCCCACCCUUCAGGCUGCACUGUGUGUGAAGUAGCCACCUGCCCUGCCUCCCUCCUCCCCGUUGGCCCCUGUUUGGACUUAGUGCCUGUCUGGCAGCCUGUGGGGUCAGGAGAAGCACCCCCAGGGCAGCCCUCUUGACUGGCGCAGUGGGAAGAGGCCUUCAGCCCCUCUCCCGGAGAUGGAAUCGCGGGGCAGGGAGGGGCAGGGUGUUCUAGAGGUGAGAAGAGGGCCUGGUGGAGAUUCCCUGUCUUCUGAGCCCGAGCCCCUCAUUACCAGUGAAGGACAUGCUUGAGGGGUUCGGGAAGCUCCUCAUCUGAGGCAACUGGUCCUGGGGGUGCUCAGGCCUGCCUUUUUGGGACUCAGAUGGCAGGAGGUCCACCCCGCAGCCUGGUCCUCGGCUCUCCCACAGGUGGGCACCCCCCACUUUGGUGCUAAUAGCUCUCCACCAGGUGGUGUGAGCGCGGGGGCUGCCAGAAGCGGGAGGGGUCACUGCCGGAAGAGCAGCUGCCCUCCGACCCCUCACUUUGUGCCUUUAGUAAACACUGUGCUUUGUA